CUCCGCACUGCUCACUCCCGCGCAGUGAGGUUGGCACAGCCACCGCUCUGUGGCUCGCUUGGUUCCCUUAGUCCCGAGCGCUCGCCCACUGCAGAUUCCUUUCCCGUGCAGACAUGGCCUCUGGCACCACCACCACCGCCGUGAAGGUGAGAUGAGCCCUCCCAGCCGCAGCGGUUCGCCCUGCCGGAUGCCUUCUCGCCCCCGCGCCGGGGGACCGCGCCUCCGGGGGCCAUGCGCCCGGCCCGUGCGUCCCUUGCCGCCGCGGGGAGGGACUGGGGCGCGGCACUCGGGACUCACUUGCCGCGCGAGGAGAGGAUUGGAAUAAUUGGUGGAACAGGCCUGGAUGAUCCAGAAAUUUUAGAAGGAAGAACUGAAAAAUAUGUGGAUACUCCAUUUGGCAAGCCAUCUGAUGCCUUAAUUUUGGGGAAGAUAAAAAAUGUUGAUUGCGUCCUCCUUGCAAGGCAUGGAAGGCAGCACACCAUCAUGCCUUCAAAGGUCAACUACCAGGCGAACAUCUGGGCUUUGAAGGAAGAGGGCUGUACACAUGUCAUAGUGACCACAGCUUGUGGCUCCUUGAGGGAGGAGAUUCAGCCCGGCGAUAUUGUCAUUAUUGAUCAGUUCAUUGACAGGACCACUAUGAGACCUCAGUCCUUCUAUGAUGGAAGUCAUUCUUGUGCCAGAGGAGUGUGCCAUAUUCCAAUGGCUGAGCCGUUUUGCCCCAAAACGAGAGAGGUUCUUAUAGAGACUGCUAAGAAGCUAGGACUCCGGUGCCACUCAAAGGGGACAAUGGUCACAAUCGAGGGACCUCGUUUUAGCUCCCGGGCAGAAAGCUUCAUGUUCCGCACCUGGGGGGCGGAUGUUAUCAACAUGACCACAGUUCCAGAGGUGGUUCUUGCUAAGGAGGCUGGAAUUUGUUACGCAAGUAUCGCCAUGGCGACAGAUUAUGACUGCUGGAAGGAGCACGAGGAAGCAGUUUCGGUGGACCGGGUCUUAAAGACCCUGAAAGAAAACGCUAAUAAAGCCAAAAGCUUACUGCUCACUACCAUACCUCAGAUAGGGUCCACAGAAUGGUCAGAAACCCUCCAUAACCUGAAGAAUAUGGCCCAGUUUUCUGUUUUAUUACCAAGACAUUAAAGUAGCAUGGCUGCCCAGGAGAAAAGAAGACAUUCUAAUUCCAGUCAUUUUGGGAAUUCCUGCUUAACUUGAAAAAAAUAUGGGAAAGACAUGCAGCUUUCAUGCCCUUGCCUAUCAAAGAGUAUGUUGUAAGAAAGACAAGACAUUGUGUGUAUUAGAGACUCCUGAAUGAUUUAGACAACUUCAAAAUACAGAAGAAAAGCAAAUGACUAGUAAACAUGUGGGAAAAAAUAUUACAUUUUAAGGGGGAAAAAAAAACCCACCAUUCUCUUCUCCCCCUAUUAAAUUUGCAACAAUAAAGGGUGGAGGGUAAUCUCUACUUUCCUAUACUGCCAAAGAAUGUGAGGAAGAAAUGGGACUCUUUGGUUAUUUAUUGAUGCGACUGUAAAUUGGUACAGUAUUUCUGGAGGGCAAUUUGGUAAAAUGCAUCAAAAGACUUAAAAAUACGGACGUACUUUGUGCUGGGAACUCUACAUCUAGCAAUUUCUCUUUAAAACCAUAUCAGAGAUGCAUACAAAGAAUUAUAUAUAAAGAAGGGUGUUUAAUAAUGAUAGUUAUAAUAAUAAAUAAUUGAAACAAUCUGAAUCCCUUGCAAUUGGAGGUAAAUUAUGUCUUAGUUAUAAUUAGAUUGUGAAUCAGCCAACUGAAAAUCCUUUUUGCAUAUUUCAAUGUCCUAAAAAGACACGGUUGCUCUAUAUAUGAAGUGAAAAAAGGAUAUGGUAGCAUUUUAUAGUACUAGUUUUGCUUUAAAAUGCUAUGUAAAUAUACAAAAAAACUAGAAAGAAAUAUAUAUAACCUUGUUAUUGUAUUUGGGGGAGGGAUACUGGGAUAAUUUUUAUUUUCUUUGAAUCUUUCUGUGUCUUCACAUUUUUCUACAGUGAAUUUAAUCAAAUAGUAAAGUUGUUGUAAAAAUAAAAGUGGAUUUAGAAAGAUCCAGUUCUUGAAAACACUGUUUCUGGUAAUGAAGCAGAAUUUAAGUUGGUAAUAUUAAGGUGAAUGUCAUUUAAGGGAGUUACAUCUUUAUUCUGCUAAAGAAGAGGAUCAUUGAUUUCUGUACAGUCAGAACAGUACUUGGGUUUGCAACAGCUUUCUGAGAAAAGCUAGGUGUUUAAUAGUUUAACUGAAAGUUUAACUAUUUAAAAGACUAAAUGCACAUUUUAUGGUAUCUGAUAUUUUAAAAAGUAAUGUUUGAUUCUCCUUUUUAUGAGUUAAAUUAUUUUAUACGAGUUGGUAAUUUUUGCUUUUUAAUAAAGUGGAAGCUUGCUUUUUUAACUCUUUUUUUAUUGUUAUUUUAUAGAAAUGCUUUUUGUUGGCCGGGCACAGUUGCUCAUCCAUGUAAUCCCAGCACUGUGGGAGGCCGAGACGGGUGGAUCACAAGGUCAGGAGAUCGAGACCAUCCUGGCUAAUGCGUUGAAACUCCGUCUCUACUAAAAAUACAAAAAAUUAGCUGGGCGUGGUGGUGGGCACCUGUAGUCCCAGCUACUCAGGAGGCUGAGGCAGGAGAAUGGUGUGAACCUGGGAGGUGGAGCUUGCAGUGAGCAGAGCUUGCAGUGAGACGAGCUUGUGCCACUGCACUCCAGCCUGGGCAACAGAGUAAGACUCAGUCUCAAAAAAAAAAAAAAGAGUGAAAUGCUUUUUGUUUGCUUCAGUUUUUUAUCAUGGGGAGAUCUUUUUCCUCAGAAUUGUUUUCUUUUCACUGUAGGCUAUUACAGGAUACUUCAGGAUCAAGAUACAGAACCUUUUAUUUAAAGAGUUUGUAAAGUCAAUGUGUUUGUUUGUGUCUCUGAGAUUGACUUCAAGAUAAUAAGCUGCUAAUUGUAAACAAAACAGUUACCCUCCAGUAUUAAUAUGACUCAUUAGUGUGAGCCAUUUGGGUCAAGUAUGAUUAUGACCCUUGGACUUCCUGAUGUAGUAUUAAAUUUCAACUCUGGUUAUCCAUUAGCAAUCUGUAGAGAACUUAAUGAACCUGAACCCAGGCUUCUCUAGCUCUGGUAACGUGUGAUUGUUUUCACUACAAUAUGAUACAUAGAUGGUACCUUACUUUUCCUCAUUCUUAAUAGGUGUCUAAGAAUGUCAGGGCAAAAGUAUGGGCAUUUUUCUUGCUAUGUUCAGAAAGUACAGUUCUCUCCAACUUGCAGAGGUACUUUUCUUGAUUAAAUAGCCUUCUCUAGCAACAUCAUUUUCAGACUAACUAAAUGAAUGCAGUAUACUCUUUUCUUUGUUCUCAAUCAUUCACUCCUUAUGCAAAGCCAAUAUAAUUUUCCUCAUACCUUAUGCUUGAGGAUAUUGUUGAAGAACACUUCCUGGAACACUUCUCACUUGUGAUGCUGUACUAAUUUUUUUUUUUUAAUUUAAGCUAGUAUACUAAGUGAACACCAUGGUCAGUUGUGAGCAUUUUGGUUUCCGCAAAGGAUGGAUGGUGAGCAUCAUGGGAAAGCUGUAGUUUAGUGACUUAGCCCUUAGUGAUUAAUAGAUUUGCAUGUACAUAGAAGUCUUUGUUGGCCUUAUAAUCUGCUGUUAUAUUUGGCAUGGAUUUUCAUGGUUUUGAGAAUGACAUCCUGGCCCUGUGGUCCCCGAGGGUCAUGGUCCUUGUGACCUGGCCCCUGUUCACUGCCCCCUUCGCUAGCACGAGUUGCUGUGCAGGGCUGGAGGUAGCUACCAUGGCUUGUUUCAAGGAAGGAAACUCUGGUACGGUGGCACCCUCAGGAGUGGAGGACAGUGAACUUCCUUGAAGAGGGAGUGACUAAGGUGACCUCCAACCUGCCCUGAGCCAGCUGCCCUGCAGGUGCCACGUGAGCCUGCUCUGGCAUCCACAGGAUGCUCCUGGAGCCUCUUCUCUGGCUGCUACCUCAGGGCAUGGUUGUGGCCCCACCAACACCUAUUUUCCAAAUAAUUAUUCAUUCUUGUGACAGUGGCCUGAACAUGUUUUUAAUUUUCUCAACAAGCAUUUAGCCAGCACUUAUCCAGUGAAACAAUUUGAUAAGGUUUCAAGGAGUAUCUGAUGGGUUAGGAAGUCACGAAAUGAGGAGUUCUUGCCACAUUUGCAGAGUCCCUCCUUGAUAAGGUUUGGCGGUGUCCCCACCCAAAUCUCAUGUUGAAUUGUAGUUCCCAUAAUCCCCACAUGUUGUGGGAGGGACCCAGUGGGAGGUAAUUAAAUCAUGGGGGUGGUUACCCCCACACUGCUGUUCUCAUGAUACUGAGUUCUCACAAGUCCUGUUUGUUUUAUAAGGGGCUUUUCCCCCUUUUGCUCAACACUUCUUCCUGCCAUCAUGUGAAGAAGGACGUGUUUGUUUCCCCUUCUGCCACGAUUGUAAGUUUCCUGAGGCCUUCCCAGCUAUGUGGAACUGUGAGUUAAUUAAACCUCUUUCCUUUAUAAAUUACCCAGUCAUGGGCAGUCCUUUACAGCAGCAUGAGAAUGGACUAAUACACUCCUCAAAUGUUUUGAAGAUUGUUGCACCUUGGAACUACCAGUGUGCACACAAUCUGGCUCAAUGUAUAUAUUGGCCCAGCAAGGCAAAGAACUGAAGUUCCAGGAUGGAAGAACCUGUGUUCUCCUCAUAAUAGUAUAGAAUAAUUCAAGAUAGGCAAGAAGGACAGCAGUAAAUGAAGACCAUGGAAGAAAAGAAGGAAUGCCAAAGAUCGAGGAAAUCUACCAAGACUAGUAGGGUAGUCCAGAAGAAGCUGUUUCAGGGCCUGUUGCCAGCUAUGCCUUUGAGAACCUCGGGAUCCCAAAGAAUGAGGGGAAUUUCUUCAGAAAGACAAUCUCGGCAUGCAUUAUUUCUUUGUUUUGAAGAUUCACUCAUGUUGCAUGCAUCUGUAGCUUGUGCCUUUUUUAUUGCCUAGUAGUAUUCUGUCAUAUGCCUAUCUUACAAUUUGAUUAUCUAUUCACCUGUUGAUGAAUGUUUGAAUUUUUUCCAUUUGAGGAAUUUUAUGAAUAAAGCUGCUAUAAGCAUGAAAUUACAAGUCUUUUUGUGAACAUAUUUUCACUUGUGCAAAUGCCUAUACUCCCACCAGUAAUUUGUAAGAAUUCUUGACAAAGCUUGGUAUUGUCAGCGUUUUUAAUUUUAGCCAUUCUAUUGGGUAUAUUUUGAUAUCUCGUGGUUUUGAUUUGCAUUUUUCUGAUUAAAGAUGUUGAACUUCUUUUCAUGUGCUUAUUGGCCAUUCACAUAUUUCGUGAACUAUCUGUACAAAUAUUUUUGUUUAUUAAAAAAUUAGAUUGUUUUGUUUUAUUAUUGAAUAGUAAGAAUUGUUUAUAUAUUCUGGAUACACUCUUUUUCAGAUAUGUGUGUUGUGACUAUUCUUAGUCUUUAGCUUGCCUUUUCAUUUUCUUAAUUAUGUCUUUCAAAGAACAAGUUUUUCAUUUUGACGAAGCCUAGUUUAUCAAUUUUUUUUAUGGUUGGUGCUUUUUGUGUGUUCCAAGAAAUCUUUGCCUACUCAUUUAAUUACCUGUGUGCCCUUGUCAAAAUCAUUUAAUUUUGACUACUCACUUAAUUACCUUGCCUACUCAUUUAAUUACCUGUGUGCCCUUGUCAAAAUUUACUGUUUAUCUGUGAAUCUGGAUGAUCUAUUUAUGUCAUUUAUCUAUGUGUCUCUUCUUAUGCCAGUACCCCACUGUCUUGAUUAUUGUGGCUUUAUGGUGUCUUGAAAUUAAGUAUUGUUAAGCUUUGCAAUCUUUUCCAAGAUUGUUUUGGCUAUAGGUCCUUUCUUUAUAAAGUUUAUAUUAAGCUUCUCCAUUUUUCUUUAAGAAAAAAUCUGCUGGAAUGGCACUGAAUUUUUAGGUCGAUUUGGGAAGAAUUGACAAUAUUGAACCUUUCAAUCGAUGGACAUGGUAUGUUUCUGCAUUUAUUUGGGCCUUUUAAAAUUUAUCUCAGCAAUAUUUUGUAGUUUUAGUGAAGAAGUCUUGUAUAUAUCUUUUGUUAAAUGUAUUCCUAAAUAUUUUGUGGAAAUGUUACUGUAAAUAGUACUUUAAUUUCAUUUUUAAGUUUAUUGCUGGUAUACAGAAAUAUGUUUUAUUUUUGUAUAUUGACUUUAUAUUCUGUAAUCUUAUUAAAUUCACUUAGUUCAGUA